ACACCCCUGCCAGCGGCACCAUGGCUUUCCUCUGGCUCCUCUCCUGCUGGGCCCUCCUGGGUACCACCUUCGGCUGCGGGGUCCCCGCCAUCCACCCUGUGCUCAGCGGCCUGUCCAGGAUCGUGAAUGGGGAGGACGCCGUCCCCGGCUCCUGGCCCUGGCAGGUGUCCCUGCAGGACAAAACCGGCUUCCACUUCUGCGGGGGCUCCCUCAUCAGCGAGGACUGGGUGGUCACCGCUGCCCACUGCGGGGUCAGGACCUCCGACGUGGUCGUGGCUGGGGAGUUUGACCAGGGCUCUGACGAGGAGAACAUCCAGGUCCUGAAGAUCGCCAAGGUCUUCAAGAACCCCAAGUUCAGCAUUCUGACCGUGAACAAUGACAUCACCCUGCUGAAGCUGGCCACACCUGCCCGCUUCUCCCAGACAGUGUCCGCCGUGUGCCUGCCCAGCGCCGACGACGACUUCCCCGCGGGGACACUGUGUGCCACCACAGGCUGGGGCAAGACCAAGUACAACGCCAACAAGACCCCUGACAAGCUGCAGCAGGCAGCCCUGCCCCUCCUGUCCAAUGCCGAAUGCAAGAAGUCCUGGGGCAGGAGGAUCACCGACGUGAUGAUCUGUGCCGGGGCCAGUGGCGUCUCCUCCUGCAUGGGUGACUCUGGAGGCCCCCUGGUCUGCCAGAAGGACGGAGCCUGGACCCUGGUGGGCAUUGUGUCCUGGGGCAGCCGCACCUGCUCUACCACCACGCCCGCUGUGUACGCCCGUGUCGCCAAGCUCAUACCCUGGGUGCAGAAGAUCCUGGCCGCCAACUGAGCCCGCAGCUCCUGCCACCCCUGCCUUAAGAUUUCCCAUUAAAUGCAUCUGUUUAGAA